GCCAACCAGAAUCUUUCCCAACUUGUCUAAGUCCUCUCAGGCCAGCCUUGGUGGGAGGUUUCUAGGAUUCGCUCCCUGCCCUUCCCAUCUUAGGGUGUCGUCUGAGACAGACUCUUAUUCCCUCAAUAAAGAGAGAGACUCUUAUUCCCUCAGCGGCCAGCUCCUCGCCUCCCCUCGGCCGUAGCCACCUCAGUGGUCACCGUCUUCACCGUGGUCGCCUCAGCCCGCUCGCCACCCCAGUUGAGGCGCUGCUGGUGUCAUGUCUGCCACAGGGGACCGACACCCGACCCAAGGGGACCAGGAGGCCCCGGUAAGCCAGGAGGGAGCACAGGCCGAGGCGGCCGGAGCUGGUAACCAGGAGGGCGGCGACUCCGGCCCCGACAGCAGCGACGUGGUGCCUGCGGCCGAGGUGGUCGGAGUCGCAGGGCCCGUGGAAGGCCUCGGGGAGGAGGAGGGUGAGCAGGCGGCAGGCCUGGCCGCAGUCCCCCGGGGCGGGAGCGCCGAGGAGGACUCAGAUAUCGGGCCCGCGACGGAGGAAGAGGAGGAGGAAGAGGGGAACGAGGCGGCCAACUUCGACUUGGCGGUGGUCGCCCGUCGCUACCCGGCGUCGGGCAUUCACUUCGUGCUCCUGGACAUGGUCCACUCCCUUCUCCACCGCCUCUCUCACAACGACCACAUCCUCAUAGAGAACCGUCAACUCAGCCGCCUGAUGGUGGGGCCACACGCUGCUGCGCGCAACCUCUGGGGCAACCUCCCCCCGCUGCUGCUGCCCCAGAGGCUGGGUGCAGGGGCCGCAGCCCGGGCGGGCGAGGGCCUGGGCCUGAUCCAGGAGGCCGCAUCGGUCCCAGAGCCUGCAGUGCCAGCUGACCUGGCCGAGAUGGCCAGGGAGCCCGCGGAGGAGGCCGCAGAGGAGAAGCUCUCAGAGGAGGCCACAGAGGAACCAGACGCAGAGGAACCGGCCACAGAAGAACCGACCGCACAGGAGGCCACGGCCCCAGAGGGAGAUCUGAGAUCAUCGGUGCCAUUUGUGAGCCCGCAGAUGAAUGGCCGGGUAGAUAGGGGUUCAGGAGGGAGCUCCGCAGGAAACAGAAGGGAUGCGCCAAGGAAAAGAACAGGCAAAUGGCAGGCAUCCCUUUUAGUUCAUGGCUUUUCAAAGUGUAAAGAUUCGUAGAAAGUUGAUCCCCCAAAUGAUGAAGUGAUGCAGGAGCACUUGGUAAAAAUGAAGCAUUCGGGGGGGUGAGGAACCAAUGAGCUUCACCAUAGAAUUUGUCUUUUGAGGUAAACAAAUAUUUUCCCAACAAAGUUCUGACCAAAACACCGUAGAAUGAGAUCGGACCCGAUGAUUCAGAUCUCUUCUUCUCCAAAGAACUAGAAAUAAUCAGCCGCUUUGGGUGGGAGAUUUACUGGAAAAAAGGGAAAUACAGUGUCCCUGUGGAAAUGAUCAAGCAGCA